AGUGAGGAGGUGGUUCUUGCCCGUGUUGUGUGUGUGUGUGAGUGAGAGAGCGAGUGAGUGAGUGAGUGAGUGUGUGUGUGGGGGGGACUCGGCUUGUUGUUGUCGGUGACUUCCCCCUCCCCUUCACCCCUUCCCCUCCCCGCCGCCGCUGCAGUGGCCGCUCCCUGGGCCGUAGGAAAUGAGCGAUAACGAUGACAUCGAGGUGGAGAGCGACGAAGAGCAACCGAGGUUUCAAUCUGCGGCUGACAAACGGGCUCAUCAUAAUGCACUGGAACGAAAACGUAGGGACCACAUCAAAGACAGCUUUCACAGUUUGCGGGACUCAGUCCCAUCACUCCAAGGAGAGAAGGCAUCCCGGGCCCAAAUCCUAGACAAAGCCACAGAAUAUAUCCAGUAUAUGCGAAGGAAAAACCACACACACCAGCAAGAUAUUGACGACCUCAAGCGGCAGAAUGCUCUUCUGGAGCAGCAAGGUGCUCUGCCUGCAGUAGGGAUCACACCUGGCAUCAGGUGUCUGAAAAGAGCUUUGAGGUCCUUGGAGUGGAAUGUGCUGUGGGAAAGCGAGAGCUGAUCAAGUUCUUUGUUCCUGGGGAAUUCACUUCUCUUCCUCCCUCAUGGAAGAUGCAAGUAAAAGGAAAUGCAAGUAACCACCUGGUCCGUGCACUGGAGAAGGCGAGGUCAAGUGCCCAACUGCAGACCAACUACCCCUCCUCAGACAACAGCCUCUACACCAACGCCAAGGGCAGCACCAUCUCUGCCUUCGAUGGGGGCUCGGACUCCAGCUCGGAGUCUGAGCCUGAAGAGCCCCAAAGCAGGAAGAAGCUCCGGAUGGAGGCCAGCUAAGCCACUCGGGGCAGGCCAGCAAUAAAAACUGUCUGUCUCCAUCGUCUCAUCCUCCUUUCAGUUCGUUGGUAGAGCCCUCAGAACCAUUUAAGAGACUCUUUAUUUUUCUCUUUCUCCCUUUUUUUUUUAAAUUUUUAUUUUUACGUAGAAGCUCUUGGACAACAGCUCUCGUUCUCCUUCCCCAUUUCCACUGUAUAUUUUUUAAUGUAUUCCCUUCAGGGAUUCCCUGUCCCCAACAGGAAUUUUUAAACCAAAACACCCCAACUUGGCAGCUUUUUCUGUGGAGGACAGACGGCCGGCCGGACCUCUGAGCACAUAGUGUCCUGCCCACCCUACCAGCUCCUCCAGCCCUGCCGGGCACAUGCCCGGGGGACGCCUGCCCUGCCCAGGUGGCCUCCUGGCCCGCCCUCACCUCUGAUAGACUUUGUGAAUCUGAACUGCUCUACUUUGAGAAGAUGACCGGUUUGGAGUAAUCAGAAUGAACCCUCCUCCUUUUUAAGGGUUUUUUUUUUUUCCUUUUUCUAAAAAGCUAUGUAUCGCUCCUAUUGAAAGACCAGAUCCUUAGAGAAGUUUGUGGUAUAAAAAGGAAGUGGGGACAGAUUCGCAGCACAGAGUCGCUGGCAUGUUUCACUCCUGCUUCUCUCAGCCAGCUGUUUAAGCCUGCGGCGCCAGCCUCACGGAGGGCCGUGUGACACUCUCGUGGUAUGUAUGGGAGAUGGCAGCAGUGAAGCAGCAGCCACCAGGGAGUGGCCAUUUGGGGUUGGGACAGGGAGGGUGUUUUGGGUGGCAUAGAGGUUUUGUAUUGAGGGCCAGUGAUGAUGUUUUGAUAUUUAUUUCCUGCUACUUAAAUUUGAAUCUGAGUGAAUUGUACCUAUUUCUGAUGAUGUCGGUCUUGCAAAGCGACAGAUUCAUAAAGUAAUGAUGAAAUCUUUCUUUCUUCCCGUGUGUAUUUCUAAGAAAUAGAGCCAACUGAUUUUGUAUGUAAAUACCAAGAGCAAUUUACCUGGUACUAAACCCGCACCCCAGUGCGGACCCUUCCCAGCCCUCAUCCCACUUCCUUUCCUACUGUCCUGGAACCUGUCUCCAUUGUGUGAUCCAGCCCUGGUUCUGGCUGUGGUCAGCAGAUGCCAGUGAAGGGUUUUGUGUGUUUAGGCCUCAUUUCUUUGUCUUUUUCCUACUCCGUUCCUGGCAUUUGCUGAUUUCUAGUGUAUACUCUGUAGUCUCAGUUCGUGUUUGAUUCCAUUCCAUGGAAAUAAAAAGUAUGUUGUACAUACUGCCGAAGAAUUGUCUUGCAAGUUAAGGCUUCCCCCUUUACUAUAAGACUAUAAAUAAAAACUUAUUUUAUCCUU